GCGCACCCGGAUCCCGGCUCCUGCAUCCAGUCGCCAUUCGGGAGGCCGCUGCGCUGCAGGGCCUCGCGGAGCCGCCCGCGACCGCGAGCCGGGCCCUCCGCGCGGUCCAUCGCCCACUGGACGCCGCCCGCGGCCGGACCGGUUCAACUUCUCAUCUUUGUUCUUCUUCAUAUACUAUAGGCUGUUUGCUGUGGUUUAGUCAAAAAGCCAUGUAGAAUGCCUGCCUUUUGAAGACCACUUUUAAGGUGUCUAGUAAGACAGCAGAUGGAGUCUUGCUCUGUCACCAGGCUGGAAUGCAGCGGCAUGAUCUCAGCUCUCUGCAACCUCCGACUUCUGGUCCAAGCGAUUGGCCUGCCUCAGCCUCCCAAGUAGCUGGGACUACAGGCACACGCCACCACGCCUGGCUAAUUUUUGUAUUUUUAGUAGAGAUGGGGUUUCACCAUGUUGGCCAUGAUGGUCUUGAUCUCCCGACCUCGUGAUCUGCCUGCCCGGCCUCCCAAAGUGCUGAGAUUACAGGCAUGAGCCACUGCGCCCAGCCUAUACAUUUUUUUAAAAUAAUGGUUUUGUAAUUAAUAAAGGGAGAGCCUGCAUUUCUAAUCUGUACUGUUCUUUGAGGAGGAGUAAAUAUCAUUACCGUCAAUAAGGGAAGGUGUUCAGUCUUUCUCAUUAAAGAGAAGCACAUUAACACAAUAGUGAAAUACUAGCUUUCACCUAGGUUGUAGCAAGGAUUAGGAAUUUAUAGGAAAUUGUCUCUCAUAUAUACACGUUGUUAUGCAGUAAUAGAAGUUUUUGAGAGUUUGGUAAAAUGUAUCAAUUUUACACACAAAUGGCCAAGUAAUCCAUUGCUAGGAAUUUUCCCUGCAGAAAUACCCUCACAUGCACAGAUAAGUACAGGGAAAGUCAGUGCUUAUUCCAUAUGUAAAAAUGUCUUAGAGAUAAAUUCUAAAUGAGAGUAAGUUGCCAGAUAAUAUGUUUAAUAUCCCAUUUGUGUAAAGCAUGUGUGUUGAUCAAUAUAUGCUUAGGACAUUUCUUCCAGGACACAUGAGUACACUGGCUACCCCUAGGGACUGACACUCUGUAUCUCGUACUGUGUGAAUGUGUUUUUAACUGUGAGCUUCUAUUCCCUUUACUACUUAAGAAGACUGGUUUACAAUUUUUUUAAAUUCAUGUUUUCCGGCAACUGUGUUCCAGCUGCUGGGGUGUCCUCUGAUUUGCCCUUUGGUUGGUAUGCGCCUUCACAUCAUUCAGGAUCUCUGCUGGAAUGUCCCAUGCAUAGAGGUCUUUUCCAACGGCCUCUACAUCACUCUCCACCUUAUCUUUCCAACUCAUGAACGCCAUAUUGCAAAGCACUGCUUUAAGCCUAAGUGCCUAGAACAUUGUAGGACACAAAGUUAUUUAUUUAUUAAAUGAAUUAAUAGAAUACUAUAUUGGGAUAGAUUAAACAUUACAAAAUAUGUUGACAUGAAAUCAAGCCAGCAUCAUGUUUUAAAGUCAUCUUUUUAUAGCUAGAUUUAAUUUAUUAAGUGCUUUCUGCAAAAGUUUUAGUCUCUUGUUCAUCCUUAAAUAGCCAAGAUUUAAUUUUGAUAUUCACUCAUCUUUGUGUGCUGAGGACUUUUGUACUCGGAGUUUGAGAGUCAAAGUAUAAAGCACAUGCAAUAGCUAAUUCUAGAGUCAGGCUCACAUCACUGAUAGUCCUAUAGCCUGGACCAGAGAAAGUCAGGUAACUUCUCUGAACCUGUUUCUUCAUCUGUAAGUGAAAAUAAUAGUUGAGUCAUAUCAUUAGGAUUAAAUGAGAUGAUGUAUGUGAAACUCCUAGCAGAGUGCCUGGGACUGUUCUAUAUCUCCUUUUUCUUCAAAUUCUCCCUAGAGAUACUAUCAAAUAAAGCACGCACUGUUCUAGACUUAAAAUUAUGCAGUUAUAGAAUGGACUGACAGCAUUUUAUUCAGAAUUACAGUUCAUGAAAAUAAUUUAUUCCUACUUUAUUGCAGCAGUAUUGAAAGUUUUUAAAGAAUAUAACCGUGUGUGUUGGUAACAGACAGAAGAAUGGAAGCAUUCCAGGAACUUCGUAAACCAUCAGCACGUUUGGAGUGUGACCAUUGCAGUUUCAGAGGCACAGACUAUGAAAAUGUACAAAUCCAUAUGGGUACCAUCCAUCCAGAAUUUUGUGAUGAAAUGGAUGCUGGUGGGCUAGGCAAAAUGAUAUUUUACCAGAAAAGUGCAAAGUUAUUUCACUGCCAUAAAUGCUUCUUCACCAGCAAGAUGUACUCUAAUGUAUACUAUCACAUCACAUCCAAACAUGCAUCCCCAGACAAAUGGAAUGAUAAACCAAAAAAUCAGUUGAACAAAGAAACAGAUCCUGUGAAAAGCCCUCCUCUUCCUGAACACCAGAAAAUACCCUGCAAUUCAGCAGAACCAAAAUCCAUACCUGCCCUUUCAAUGGAAACACAGAAACUUGGUUCAGUUUUGUCUCCAGAAUCGCCAAAACCUACUCCUCUUACUCCCCUGGAGCCUCAGAAACCUGGCUCUGUUGUUUCUCCUGAGCUACAGACACCUCUUCCUUCUCCUGAGCCUUCAAAACCUGCCUCUGUUUCUUCUCCUGAACCUCCAAAAUCAGUCCCUGUUUGUGAGUCUCAGAAACUUGCCCCUGUUCCUUCUCCAGAACCACAGAAACCUGCCCCUGUAUCUCCUGAGUCAGUAAAGGCUACUCUUAGUAAUCCCAAACCCCAGAAGCAGUCUCAUUUCCCGGAAACAUUGGGGCCACCUUCAGCCUCAUCUCCAGAGUCACCAGUUCUAGCUGCUUCCCCAGAACCUUGGGGACCAUCCCCAGCUGCAUCUCCAGAAUCUCGGAAGUCAGCCCGGACUACCUCCCCUGAGCCAAGGAAGCCAUCCCCUUCAGAGUCUCCUGAACCUUGGAAGCCGUUCCCUGCUGUCUCCCCAGAGCCUAGGAGACCAGCCCCCGCUGUGUCACCAGGCUCUUGGAAACCAGGGCCACCUGGGUCCCCUAGGCCUUGGAAAUCCAAUCCUUCAGCAUCAUCAGGACCUUGGAAGCCAGCUAAACCUGCUCCAUCUGUGUCUCCUGGACCUUGGAAACCAAUUCCUUCUGUAUCUCCUGGACCUUGGAAACCAACUCCAUCUGUGUCUUCUGCAUCCUGGAAAUCUUCAUCAGUCUCACCCAGCUCCUGGAAGUCUCCCCCUGCAUCUCCUGAGUCAUGGAAGUCUGGCCCACCAGAACUCCGAAAGACAGCUCCCACGUUGUCUCCUGAACAUUGGAAGGCAGUUCCCCCAGUGUCUCCAGAGCUUCGCAAACCCGGCCCACCACUAUCCCCAGAGAUCCGUAGUCCAGCAGGAUCUCCAGAGCUCAGAAAACCCUCAGGGUCACCAGAUCUUUGGAAGCUUUCUCCUGAUCAGCGGAAAACUUCUCCUGCUUCACUUGAUUUCCCUGAGUCCCAGAAAAGUUCCCGUGGUGGUUCUCCUGAUCUCUGGAAGUCUUCCUUUUUUAUUGAGCCUCAGAAACCUGUCUUCCCUGAGACCCGAAAACCAGGUCCUUCUGGGCCAUCUGAGUCCCCCAAAGCAGCCUCAGAUAUCUGGAAGCCUGUUCUCUCUAUCGAUACUGAGCCUAGAAAACCUGCCCUGUUUCCCGAGCCUGCCAAAACAGCCCCUCCUGCUUCUCCAGAAGCACGCAAACGUGCCCUUUUUCCAGAGCCCCGGAAGCAUGCCCUUUUCCCUGAACUCCCCAAAUCUGCUCUAUUCUCAGAAUCACAGAAGGCUGUUGAGCUUGGUGAUGAACUACAAAUAGAUGCCAUAGAUGAUCAAAAAUGUGAUAUUUUGGUUCAGGAAGAACUUCUAGCUUCACCUAAGAAACUCUUAGAAGAUACUUUAUUUCCUUCCUCAAAGAAGCUCAAGAAAGACAACCAAGAGAGCUCAGACGCUGAGCUUAGUAGUAGUGAGUACAUAAAAACAGAUUUGGAUGCGAUGGAUAUUAAGGGCCAGGAAUCAAGCAGUGAUCAAGAGCAGGUUGAUGUGGAAUCCAUUGAUUUUAGCAAAGAGAACAAAAUGGACAUGACUAGUCCAGAGCAGUCUAGAAAUGUGCUACAGUUUACUGAAGAAAAAGAAGCUUUUAUCUCUGAAGAGGAGAUUGCAAAAUACAUGAAGCGUGGAAAAGGAAAGUAUUAUUGCAAAAUUUGUUGCUGUCGUGCUAUGAAAAAAGGUGCUGUUUUGCAUCAUUUGGUUAAUAAGCAUAAUGUUCAUAGCCCUUACAAAUGCACAAUCUGUGGAAAGGCUUUUCUUUUGGAAUCUCUCCUUAAAAAUCAUGUAGCAGCCCAUGGGCAAAGUUUACUUAAAUGUCCACGUUGUAAUUUUGAAUCAAAUUUCCCAAGAGGUUUUAAGAAACAUUUAACUCAUUGUCAAAGCCGGCAUAAUGAAGAGGCAAAUAAAAAGCUAAUGGAAGCUCUUGAACCGCCACUGGAGGAGCAGCAAAUUUGAUAACACAGUGUGAAUAUUUGUUCUACAAAGGUGUUUGUUGGAACCAUUCUUUGUAAGUAUAGCUUAUCAGAUAGCAUAGUUGGAUCAGUAGAUGACAUGUAUGGUGUACCGUGUUUCACUGUCUCAGUUGUGUUACUAAGAAUGAGCAUUUGAUCAUUUUUUUCUGGUCUCUGUCUAUGUGACUAUCUUGUAAGUCAAUAAAUUUCUGUAUAGUCCAGAUGGAUUAAACUUCUCAUUUCUUUUAAAUAUGUAUGAAUAAUAAUACAAGGAAGUAGGCAUUCCAUUUAAUAAUCAAGAGCAAGUUGUACUCAAAGCAUUCAGUUAAAGUGUAUCUGUGUGUGGAACUAAUUUCAGACAAUAGAAAAUAUUAGUUGAAAUGUUUAAGAAUUAGGCAUGAAAAAUAAAUUUGAGAAAUUUUGUUUCCUUACAUGUAUUUUUAAAUCAUAAGAGUUAUUUUCUAUCUGAUGUAAAAUUAGUUUAUAAAUCUUAAUCAGCUUCUAGAUGUUUAUUAGCUUUUAUGUCAUGAAAUGUUGGAGUCUCAGGGUUGCUGAUUUUCUGCUAAUGGGAAAAAUUGACUAAGUCUUUAAAAUAGUUUGCAGCCUUCUCCCACAGGAGACAAGUGAAAGAUAAGUGUGAUUUUAGAUCUUUCUUGUCCAUAGUUGUUUUCAGUGGAGUCUUCCAUUCUGUAUCUUACCCUAAGAUCUGGUUCUUCCCUCCCCAUCCCCACCCCCCACCCACCGCCUGCCAGCUCACACUAAUAGAUGAUUCUUAAUUGCCAAAUGUGUUAGAGUUUGUAUAUCCUACUCCUGGGCCUUACAUGUCGCCUGUUGGGGCUUAAGACCAGGUUGAUAAGUAGGAACUGAAAGUCUUCCAGAUUCACAGUAGAAAAUUUUAUAGACAUUUCUGUUAAAGAAAUAUAUCGAUUUUAUGUUUUUCAAUUAUGUUACUGUAAAUACCUUGUACCUGUUCAUGGAUUAUUUUAUUCUAAAAUAUUUUGUCAAAUGUGUAUCAACCAAAUUAAAAAGAAAGGUUUUCAUGUCA